GCGGUACGGGAAGACAGCUUUGGGAUGUCGGAAGAUCCUAGAGGUCCCAAGGUAGCUGACUUGCGAAGCUGAGGCUCCAGCCGAGGGCUCCAGGCCUCUGACCGGCCCAGCAGUGAGCGCGGCUGCCCGACGCUUCAGGGCCGGGAGCAGGGAGCGUGAGUCGCCAUGGCGACGCCGGCGGGUCUGGAGCGCUGGGUUCAGGACGAGCUGCACUCGGUGUUGGGGCUGAGCGAGCGGCACGUCGCCCAGUUUCUGAUCGGUACCGCACAGCGCUGCACCUCUGCCGAGGAGUUCGUGCAGCGCCUACGAGACACUGAUACCUUGGAUCUCAGUGGGCCGGCCCGGGACUUCGCCCUGAGACUCUGGAACAAGGUACCACGAAAGGCAGUGGUAGAAAAGCCAGCUCGGGCAGCAGAGCGAGAGGCCCGGGCCCUGCUGGAGAAGAACCGAUCUUAUAGGUUACUGGAAGACAGUGAAGAGAGCAGUGAGGAGACUGUGAGUAGGGCUGGAAGCAGCCUCCAGAAGAAACGUAAAAAGCGGAAACACCUCAGGAAGAAGCGUGAGGAAGAAGAGGAGGAAGAGGCUUCUGAGAAAGGGAAGAAGAAAACAGGGGGGAGUAAACAGCAGACAGAGAAGCCAGAGUCGGAAGAUGAGUGGGAACGGACAGAGCGUGAACGCCUUCAGGACCUGGAGGAGCGUGAUGCCUUUGCUGAGCGGGUUCGACAGCGGGACAAGGAUCGGACUCGAAAUGUCCUGGAACGGUCAGACAAGAAGGCUUAUGAAGAGGCUCAGAAGCGCCUCAAGAUGGCCGAGGAAGACCGGAAGGCCAUGGUCCCUGAGCUGCGGAAGAAAUCUCGCCGAGAGUACCUGGCUAAGCGGGAGCGAGAGAAGCUUGAGGACCUGGAGGCGGAGCUGGCUGAUGAGGAGUUCCUUUUUGGGGACGUGGAGCUGAGCCGGCACGAGCGGCAGGAGCUCAAAUAUAAGCGGCGAGUGCGGGAUCUCGCCCGGGAGUACCGGGCAGCUGGGGAGCAGGAGAAGCUGGAGGCCACCAAUCGCUACCACAUGCCCAAGGAAACCCGAGGACAGCCAGCCCGAGCUGUGGAUCUAGUGGAGGAGGAAUCAGGAGCCCCUGGGGAGGAGCAGCGGCGCUGGGAGGAGGCGCGGCUUGGGGCAGCGUCCCUGAAGUUUGGGGCCCGAGAUGCUGCCUCUCAGGAGCCCAAGUAUCAACUGGUGCUGGAGGAGGAGGAGACCAUUGAGUUUGUCCGGGCCACUCAGCUCCAGGGUGAUGAGGAGCCGUCAGCUCCACCCACUUCAACUCAGGCCCAGCAGAAAGAGUCCAUCCAGGCCGUCCGCCGCAGCCUCCCGGUGUUCCCAUUUCGAGAGGAGCUCCUGGCUGCUAUUGCAAAUCACCAAGUCCUCAUCAUUGAAGGCGAGACAGGCUCAGGGAAGACCACCCAGAUCCCGCAGUAUCUCUUUGAGGAGGGUUAUACAAACAAGGGUAUGAAGAUUGCCUGCACCCAACCCCGGAGAGUGGCUGCCAUGAGUGUGGCCGCCCGAGUGGCCCGGGAGAUGGGUGUGAAGCUUGGGAAUGAGGUUGGCUACAGCAUCCGCUUUGAGGACUGCACAUCAGAGCGAACUGUCCUCCGCUACAUGACAGAUGGGAUGCUUCUCCGGGAGUUCCUCUCUGAGCCUGACCUGGCGAGUUACAGGGUUUAGAAAACAACCAGGAUAGCAGAGCAUUGCUGCCGAGACUUGAAAUACCGUGUGAAGACCAUUUGAAAACACUUGGAAUGCUCAGCUCAGAGGGAGAAACAGGAAGCAUCCUGGUUCCCUCUAAAUAUGUGAAGGCUGUUACAUGGAAAGAAGGAUCAGAUUGUUUUAUGUGACCCUACACGACAUAGCUAGGAGCCAUGGGGAGGUUACAGGGAGACAGAUUCCAACUCAAUACCAAUGGCUGAGUAACCCUCAGAGUGGUGGAGAUUGCAGGGCCUGUCAGAGUGGUUGGACUCUGGGUCUUGGCCCUCCACACAAGUCUUGGGUAGCUUGGUCUGUGAAUAAUGAGCUCUUAGUGCUGGAAAUGGCCAAGCAGGGGUUGGUUGAACAUGUGUUGAGGGGGAAAAGGGAUUCAUGAAUGUAAUGGGGGUGGGGUCAGGCCAGCUGAACAAUAUGUGCCUUUUUGACUCUUCAGAGGCUGUGAAUUUCUGGUCUUGGAAGAUCACAGUGGAGCAAUUGGACAGAUAGGAUUUUAUCCUUCAUAUCCCUUGCAAAAGAUCUCUAAGAACCCAUGGAGAGCCAGCCAGCGCAAGAGUGUCUGAUGCAGAUGUUUUUGCCCAUCGAGCCAGCCUGCUUUGUGGAAUGGCUGGGGACUUCACCAUCACAGUUAGGCGUGGUGAUGGUGGAUGAGGCACACGAAAGGACCCUACACACAGACAUUCUCUUUGGAUUGAUCAAGGAUGUUGCUCGCUUCCGACCUGAGCUCAAGGUCCUGGUGGCUUCAGCCACAAUGGACACUGCCCGUUUUUCCACCUUCUUUGAUGACGCCCCUGUGUUUCGAAUCCCCGGACGCAGGUUUCCUGUGGACAUCUUCUACACCAAGGCUCCAGAGGCUGACUACUUGGAAGCUUGUGUAGUAUCUGUGUUGCAGAUCCAUGUGACCCAGCCCCCUGGGGAUAUCCUGGUGUUCCUGACAGGACAGGAGGAGAUUGAGGCUGCCUGUGAGAUGCUCCAGGAUCGCUGCCGCCGCCUGGGCUCCAAAAUCCGGGAGCUCCUGGUGCUGCCCAUUUAUGCCAAUCUGCCCUCUGACAUGCAGGCCCGUAUCUUCCAGCCCACACCACCUGGGGCACGAAAGGUGGUUGUGGCAACGAACAUUGCUGAGACAUCACUCACCAUUGAGGGCAUCAUUUAUGUGCUGGAUCCAGGGUUCUGUAAGCAGAAGAGCUACAACCCCCGCACAGGCAUGGAAUCGCUCACUGUCACACCCUGCAGCAAGGCCUCAGCCAAUCAGCGAGCUGGCAGGGCAGGUCGGGUGGCUGCAGGGAAGUGCUUCCGCCUGUAUACCGCCUGGGCCUAUCAGCACGAGCUUGAGGAAACCACAGUGCCUGAGAUCCAGAGGACCAGCUUGGGCAAUGUCGUGUUGCUGCUCAAGAGCUUAGGGAUCCAUGACCUAAUGCACUUUGAUUUCCUGGACCCUCCACCAUAUGAGACACUGCUGCUGGCUUUGGAGCAGCUGUAUGCUCUGGGAGCCCUCAACCACCUUGGGGAGCUCACCACGUCUGGUCGAAAGAUGGCAGAGCUGCCGGUGGACCCCAUGCUGUCCAAAAUGAUCUUAGCCUCUGAGAAGUACAGCUGUUCAGAGGAGAUCCUGACAGUGGCUGCCAUGCUCUCUGUCAACAACUCCAUCUUCUACCGACCAAAGGACAAGGUCGUCCAUGCUGACAAUGCCCGUGUCAACUUCUUUCUCCCUGGCGGUGACCACCUGGUUCUGCUAAAUGUUUACACACAGUGGGCUGAGAGUGGUUACUCUUCCCAGUGGUGCUAUGAGAACUUUGUACAGUUCAGAUCGAUGCGCCGAGCCCGGGAUGUGCGGGAACAGCUGGAAGGGCUCUUGGAACGUGUGGAAGUUGGUCUCAGUUCCUGCCAGGGGGACUAUAUCCGUGUACGCAAGGCCAUCACUGCUGGUUACUUUUACCACACGGCACGGUUGACUCGGAGUGGCUACCGCACAGUGAAACAGCAGCAGACAGUCUUCAUUCAUCCCAACUCCUCCCUCUUUGAGCAACAGCCACGCUGGCUGCUCUACCACGAACUUGUCUUGACCACCAAAGAGUUCAUGAGACAGGUACUGGAGAUUGAGAGCAGUUGGCUUCUGGAGGUGGCUCCCCAUUAUUAUAAGGCCAAGGAGCUAGAAGAUCCCCAUGCUAAGAAAAUGCCCAAAAAAAUAGGCAAAACACGAGAAGAGCUAGGGUAAGAGAAGGACGUAAACAGAACCUGACACCAGCUCCUUUUCCUUCUAUACAUUAUUUAAUACCUAUUAAAUAAAAUUAUUUUUGGAAUAAAGCUUGUGGGAACAUUUGGGAUCUAGA